AGGCGGUGGCCUGGAAGCCCGGAGCCUCAGCGCUCGCCCCUGCUCUGCCUAAGUGUCUAGAGAGCUGAGUGGGUUGCCUCGGAUCGGCCAGGCCUGGAUAUCAGCGAACAGAUGCGGAUUUCCACCAGGGGGCGCUAGGACGCCACGACCUUUCACUAUGUGCACCAGGGGGCGCUGCCGCCCGCCUUGGCCAUCCCGGGCUGGGAAGUCCGACCCUUCGAUUAAGCCCCGCCUGAUUGGGAAAGGCUCUGAGAAACUAUUUGCAUGAUCUUGAAAGAGCUGUGCUGAAUGGUUGAGGUAGGUAAGCCGAAUGUGAAACAGGCUCUCUCAUUGGCCUAAAUUCCCCCCCUCGAUCUGCGUCGCCAUCCCGGCCCUGCUGGACCCCGGGGUCAGUAGGAAGCCGCGGGGUGGUGGCGAGAGAGGACCCAGGUGUCCUGGCAGUGGGCGCCGCGGGGCACACGCUGGGCCAAGGUGCAGGCGGCCAGGGUGGGAGACUGUUCGCCCCGCCCUGAGUACUCCUAUCUUGUUUCUCCACCUGUUCGGGAGUUGGAGAUGUGCACCUAAAGGAGGCGCAUCUGGGGACGGACACAUCUGGCACUGAGGCCCUCGCCACCUGCCUCGCCACCUGGCGACCCUGACCCCACCACACUGCCUUGAGAGUCGCUCAAAAGUAGGGCCCCAGGGCUCGCAGCAGCAUGGGCACCGAGAAAGAAAGCCCAGAGCCCGACUGCCAGAAACAGUUCCAGGCUGCAGUGAGCGUCAUCCAGAACCUGCCCAAGAACGGUUCUUACCGCCCCUCCUAUGAAGAGAUGCUGCGAUUCUACAGUUACUACAAGCAGGCCACCAUGGGGCCCUGCCUGGUCCCCCGGCCCGGGUUCUGGGACCCCAUUGGACGAUAUAAGUGGUGAGCUCCCUGCUGGCUGGGCAGACAAGCCUCAGCUGUCAAGCAGCCCUCUCACAGCCCUCUGCCCCCAGGGACGCCUGGAACAGUCUGGGCAAGAUGAGCAGGGAGGAGGCCAUGUCUGCCUACAUCACUGAAAUGAAACUGGUGGCACAGAAGGUGAUCGACACAGUGCCCCUGGGUGAGGUGGCAGAGGACAUGUUUGGUUACUUCGAGCCCCUGUACCAGGUGAUCCCUGACAUGCCGAGGCCCCCAGAGACCUUCCUGAGAAGGGUCACAGGUUGGAAAGAGCAGGUUGUGAAUGGAGAUGUUGGGGCUGUUUCAGAGCCUCCCUGCCUCCCCAAGGAACCGGCACCCCCAAGCCCAGCUUCCCUCUGGGCAGUAACUCUACCAACCCCUCCACAGAGUCCCAUUCACCCAGGGACCUGGACUCCGAGGUUUUCUGUGAUUCCCUGGAGCAGCUGGAGCCUGAGCUGGUUUGGACAGAGCAGCGGGCAGCAUCUGGAGGAAAGCGUGAUCCCAGGAACAGCCCCGUGCCCCCCACAAAGAAAGAGGGGUUGCGGGGCAGCCCGCCGGGGCCCCAGGAGUUGGACGUGUGGCUGCUGGGGACAGUUCGAGCACUACAGGAGAGCAUGCAGGAGGUGCAGGCGAGGGUGCAGAGCCUGGAGAGCAUGCCCCGGCCCCCUGAGCAGAUGCAGUCUCACUCUGUCGGUCAGACUGGAGUGAAGUGGCGUGAACUCAGCUCACUGCAACCUCCGCCUCCCCGGGUUCAAGCAAUUCUCUGCCUCAGCCUCCCGAGUAGCUGGGAUUACAGGCGCCCACCACCAUGCCCGGCUAAUUUUUUUUGUAUUUUUAGUAGAGACGGGGUUUCACCAUCUUGGCCACGCUGGUCUUGAACUCCUGACCUCGUGACCACCUGCCUCGGCCUCCCAAAGUGCUGGGAUGACAGGCGUGAGCCAUCCCACCCGGUCUGCCACAGUCAUUCUUUUUUAUGCUCAGACAGUCACAACUUUGGCCAUUCAAGACCCUUUCAUACCGGAUCUUAUGUUCUUAUAACACGACCUGAUGAAUCUUUAAAAGCGACCUUGCUUUCCUGGUACAAGGCGCCCCACAUUCACUCCCACCUUCCCUGCCCCAGGCCUGGAACCAGCCACUUCUCCAAGGAGCCUUGGCUCCUUUUUAGUGGAGAAUGAUACUUGGAAACUAAAAUCUAGGUACCCAGGGUCCUCAUUUGACAUAUGUGGCACAUCCUUAACAACACAGGUCUUCAGGUCAUACCAAGGGUCAUUGCUUUGUGGCCCAGAGAAGAUGGCAUGGAAGCCGCUCCCUCUACCCGCAGCCCCGCCAGCCUCUCUUGAUACUGGGAUUGCCCUGGGGAGGAAGAUGUGGGAGGGAGUUGGCAUUCAACCUGUCAGGACCACCUGGGGGCCACUUCCUUUCUAGUGGUGCAGACUUAGGGGCAGGGUCUUUCCAAUCUUCCACUGAAUUGGAAGCAGGUUCCUAGGGAGGCUGUGCUGAGGCCUGGACUGGCCUCUGACUCCCUCCCUCUUGGCUGCAGAGGCCGCAGCCCAGGCCCAGUGCUCGGCCAUGGCCCCUUGGGCUCCCGGGGCCCGCGCUGCUCUUCUUCCUCCUGUGGCCCUUCGUCGUCCAGUGGCUCUUCCGAAUGUUUCGGACCCAAAAGAGGUGACUGUCAGUGGAGGGGUCUCUGCAGCCAACUGAGACUAUCUUGCUGUGCCCUGAGCCUUCCUAGGGUUUAGAAGAACAGCAUUCAAAAUUCCCCGUCCUGUCAGUGUUUGCCUUCGCACCUCCUCCCCUAAAGCAGCGCGGGGGGCAAAUAAGACCCCACCCCUCCCUGCAGCUUCACAGGGACGCUUCCUUCCCUCCCCGCAACCACCCCAGGCUCCCCUGGGAGGCUGCAGUUGUGGUACACGUCCCCGGUGCUGGGUUGGCCGUGACUCGGGGGCGGGGCGAUCGGGUCUCAGCCCCUGCCUUCCCCAGUCUCUGGGUCACCCGAAUUUUCCCACCCCUGCUUCUCCCCGAGGAGGUUGAGCUCUUGAGCAAGUUGGGACUUGGGCCGGGGCCUGGAAGAAUGAUUGGCUGGGAGGCCGCGGGAGGGAGGCCAGGAGGCCCGGACCAGUUGGGAGGAGUGAGCAGGCCCCGGGGGAGGGGGAUGAGCGCAGUUUGCUCGCUUUCCUCCCCUGCCGGCCCCCUCCGCCCCCACACACACUCGGGACGUCUUCAUUGAAGAUUCACUUACAAAGGAAUGUUUCACUAAAUAAAAGAAAACCAGAA